ACUCCAGCAGCUCCUGAGGCUUGAUGGAGUUGUCGGUAUAAAUGCACAGCUUUUUGGCAGUCAGUGGGCUGGACUCUUUGAGCCUGGAGGCCAGGAACAUGCAGACAGCACCCAGGAGUUGCAGAUGGGACUUUGAAGUUGGGAUCCUGGCGAAGAAACAGUCCAGGGAUAAUCUCUUCAGCCUCAAUGGUAUUUCAGGACUUCUUGGAUCAAGUUGGUGGCUUGGGGAGAUUUCAGAUCCUUCAGAUGGUUUUUCUUAUCAUCUCCACCUUUAUAGUUUGCCCUCGUGUUGUAUGGAGAAUUUCACUGCAUUCAUCCUGGUCACCACUGCUAGGUGCACAUCAUAGACAAUGUCAUCGUCUUGGACGAAGAAACUGUGAUCCUCAGCCAAGAUGCCCUCCUGAGAAUCUCUAUCUCACUGGACUCAAACCUGAGGCCACAGAAACGUUGUCACUUCAUCCAUCCCCAGUGGCAGCUCCUUCACCUGAAUGGGACAUUCCUCAAUAUGAAUGAACCAGACAUGGAACCGUGUGUGGACAGCAGGGUGUACAACAGAAGCUCCUUCCUCUCCACCAUCGUGACUGGUGGGACCUGGUAUGUGGAUCUCAGUCACUGAAUUUAGUGGCUACAUUCUUAUUCAUGGAGUGGUGGUGAAAGGCAUCCAAUAUGGCCAUUUAUCAGACAGAUGAGCAUCUCUGUUCAAAGAUCACUAUACUAAGAAAAGAAAAAGCACUUUGCCUUUGAGUCCCACAGAUUACACGUUCUGGAAAGACUGCAUACCAAGUAGCAGAUUUAUUUUAGUUUGUUUACAAAAAAAUGUGCAGACCAAAGUUCAAUGCUGCUAUUGGGGAGCUACUAAAGACAUCAAUAAGUAGAUGUCUAAUGUUUAAACACAUUUCAUUGAAAAUGGUUGGAAGUAUCUGAGCCAAUUAUUUCUUAUGUGACCCUAAAGAAAACAGAUACCUACCUGACCCCAAAACUACUUGAGGAAAUUGCUUCCGUGACCCUGCUGCAGAUGGGAGAGAGGGCCCAUUAAGAAGAGAGUGGGGUCAGGAUCAACACACACACUUAGUGUGAUUUAAGGAAAGGAAAUAUUUUCUCUUUGAACUUAUCUGGAUACAGUCAUUUUGUCUCCUCUUGGGGAUCACUUGUCCAGCCUCAAUGGCCUUUCAGGACCUCCUAGAUCAAGUUGGAGGCCUGGGGAGAUUCCAGAUCCUUCAGAUGGUUUUCCUUAUAAUGUUCAACGUCAUAGUAUACCAUCAAACUCAGCUGGAGAACUUCGCAGCAUUCAUACUUGAUCAUCGCUGCUGGGUUCAUAUACUGGACAAUGACACUAUCCCUGACAAUGACCCUGGGACCCUCAGCCAGGAUGCCCUCCUGAGAAUCUCCAUCCCAUUCGACUCAAAUCUGAGGCCAGAGAAGUGUCGUCGCUUUGUCCAUCCCCAGUGGAAGCUCAUUCAUCUGAAUGGGACCUUCCCCAACACGAGUGAGCCAGAUACAGAGCCCUGUGUGGAUGGCUGGGUAUAUGACCAAAGCUCCUUCCCUUCCACCAUUGUGACUAAGUGGGAUCUGGUAUGCGAAUCUCAACCACUGAAUUCAGUAGCUAAAUUUCUAUUCAUGGCUGGAAUGAUGGUGGGAGGCAACCUAUAUGGCCAUUUGUCAGACAGGUUUGGGAGAAAGUUCGUGCUCAGAUGGUCUUACCUCCAGCUCGCCAUUGUAGGCACCUGUGCGGCCUUUGCUCCCACCAUCCUCGUAUACUGCUCCCUGCGCUUCUUGGCUGGGGCUGCUACAUUUAGCAUCAUUGUAAAUACUGUUUUGUUAAUUGUAGAGUGGAUAACUCACCAAUUCUGUGCCAUGGCAUUGACAUUGACACUUUGUGCUGCUAGUAUUGGACAUAUAACCCUGGGAAGCCUGGCUUUUGUCAUUCGAGACCAGUGCAUCCUCCAGUUGGUGAUGUCUGCACCAUGCUUUGUCUUCUUUCUGUUCUCAAGGUGGCUGGCAGAGUCUGCUCGGUGGCUCAUUAUCAACAACAAACCAGAAGAGGGCUUAAAGGAACUUAGAAAAGCUGCACACAGGAAUGGAAUGAAGAAUGCUGAAGACAUCCUAACCAUGGAGGUUUUGAAAUCCACCAUGAAGCAAGAACUGGAGGCAGCACAGAAAAAGCAUUCUCUUUGUGAAUUGCUCCGCAUACCCAACAUAUGUAAAAGAAUCUGUUUCCUGUCCUUUGUGAGAUUUGCAAGUACCAUCCCUUUUUGGGGCCUUACUUUGCACCUCCAGCAUCUGGGAAACAAUGUUUUCCUGUUGCAGACUCUCUUUGGUGCAGUCACCCUCCUGGCCAAUUGUGUUGCACCUUGGGCACUGAAUCACAUGAGCCGUCGACUAAGCCAGAUGCUUCUCAUGUUCCUACUGGCAACCUGCCUUCUGGCCAUCAUAUUUGUGCCUCAAGAAAUGCAGACCCUGCGUGUGGUUUUGGCAACCCUGGGUGUGGGAGCUGCUUCUCUUGGCAUUACCUGUUCUACUGCCCAAGAAAAUGAACUAAUUCCUUCCAUAAUCAGGGGAAGAGCUACUGGAAUCACUGGAAACUUUGCUAAUAUUGGGGGAGCCCUGGCUUCCCUCAUGAUGAUCCUAAGCAUAUAUUCUCGACCCCUGCCCUGGAUCAUCUAUGGAGUCUUUGCCAUCCUCUCUGGCCUUGUUGUCCUCCUCCUUCCUGAAACCAGGAACCAGCCUCUUCUUGACAGCAUCCAGGAUGUGGAAAAUGAGGGAGUAAAUAGCCUAGCUGCCCCUCAGAGGAGCUCUGUGCUAUAGGUCUGUGCUGAGGAAAGCAAAACACCAUUUAGGGCUACCAUCCCCCAAAAAGGCUUAGAUCUGGGCUAUUCCCAUGUAGUCAGUGCCUUUGCCUUUGGUGUAUCCUCAUCCCUUCCACAGUGACCUCAUACAUCCCCUGAGCCUCACUAGAUCACACAGACCAUCUCUGCCCAGCCUGUCCAGGAGGUUAAUUUGUGGUGAAAAGACCAAAAUUAGGUGACCUCUGCCCUUCCUGCCCUGGUAUGACAUGCAUACUCUUGAAGGUAUUCUACAAACAUGCAGGGAUCCAAACACCAUCUUCUCAUCCCUGGGGAGCCCUCAGCCCAGUGAGUGUACCUGUUAGCUGUCUGGGAUUGCCAGUGCUUACAGGCCUGACUCCCAGGACACUGAAGAAUUUGUGAGAGACUGUAUAGAAAAUAAGAGCCCCUCCCACAGAUGAGAAGUCCUUUUGUAUCACAUGUGAGAUUCAGUCUAUCUAAUUUUCACGGGGGAAAAAAAGCGUUGGAAAAGGGGAAAAGAAGUGAUAAGUAAAGGAAUUUUUUAAGUAAUGAAGAAUGAGAAAAGGUUCUAAAACUUUUCUGUGCUUCUCUUGCCUUUUCCAAAAUCCCUUUGGUCAAUGCCAUGGUGUCCAAGUGUGAGAGUUGAAGCUAUUCAAGCUGCCUUCCCAGAUCCUAGGCUGGGAGCUUGGUUUUUUACUUCACAAGGUUUACACAAACACUUGCGGGCAGAGGCAUGUUUUUUAUUAAAGCUAGUGGGCAAAGAAUCAGUAUGUCCUAAAGAAUGCAGGACUUAUAUGUUUAGUCCAUGUCUUUCAUUUUUGAGCUUUUUUGUUUGUUGGUUUCAUUAUAUUUGCACCAGGAGAAGAUGCUCCAGAAAAGCAGGGCAGGAAGAUACCUGCAGCAAAGUGACACAAUUUUAAGGAAUUCCAGGUGCUGAUUGCUGAUUAAACAGCAAGAUAAAGGAAAAAUCGAGACCAUUUCUAGAUACUACUAAAAUUUAGAAAAUAAAUAAAUAACAAGAUAUAAUGGAUAAAUACAUUCCAUUUACAACUGUGAUUCUAAAUGGUUAAAUAUAAAAUAUCUACAAAUAAUCAUAAGAAGUUUGAAGAAAAUCAUAACACUUUAAAAGGAAUCAUAAUAGAACAUUUGUAUAAUUAUAUACAUCUCACAUGUUUCUGGAUAUGAAGAUGGAAUAAUAUUUAAAACAAUGAUUCUUCCUUAAUUAUUUAAUAGAGUAAUUGCUUAAAUAAUUACAAUGUAAAAAAUGAAAAAAGUGGAAAAACCUCAUUUUCAAGCUGCAUACUUUUAUAAGAACAUAAAAAAUAGUUCCAAAACUGGAUAUCCAUAUGCAGAAGAAUAAAACUAGAACUCUCUCACCAUAUACAAAAAUCAAAUCAAAAUGCAUUAAAAACUUGAAUCUAAGACCUCAAACUAUGAAACUGCUACAAGAAAACAUUGGAGAAAUUUUCCAGUACAUUAGACUGGCCAAAGAUUUCUUGAGUAAUACCCCACAAGUACAGGAAAACAAAGCAAAUGUGGACAAAUGGGAUCACAGCAAGUUAAAAAACUUCUGCACAGCAAAGGAUACAUUCAACAAAGUAAAGAGGCAACCCACAGAAUGGGAGAAAAUACUUGCAAACUACCCCUCUGACAAAGGACUAAUCACCAGAAUAUAUAAGGAGCUCAAACAACUCUAUAGGAAAAAUCAAAUAAUCUCAUCAAACAAUGGGCAACGUGAAUAGGUAUUUCUCAAAAGAAGACAUACAGAUGUCAAACAGUCAUAGGAAAAAGUGCUGAACAUCAUUGAUCCUCAGAGAAAUGCAAAUCAAAACUACAAUGAGAUCUCAUCUUACCUCAGUUAAAAUGGCUGAUAUCCAAAAGACAGGCAAGAACAAAUGCUGGUGAGAAUGUGGAGAAAAGGGAACCCUCAUACACUGUUGGUGGGAAUGUAAAUUAGUACAAUCACUAUGGAGAAGAGUUUGGAGAUUCCUCAAAAAAAUUAAAAAUAGAGCUAACAUUUGACCCAGCAAUUCCACUGCAUCAUUGUAUUAGUCCAUUUUCAAGCUGCUGUUAAAAACAUACCUGAGACUGGAUAAUUUACAAAGGAAAGAGGUUUAAUGGACUCACAGUUCCACAUAGCUGGUGAAGCCUCACAAUCCUGGUGGAGGGCGAAAGGCACGUCUUACAUGGCAGCAGGCAAAAAGAUAAUUUUUGCAGGGAAACUCCCUUUUAUAAAACCAUCAGAUCAUGUGAGAUUUAUUCACUAUCAUAGGAAGAGCAUGGGAAACACUCACCCCCAUGAUUCAGUUACCUCCCACUGGAUCCCUCCCAUGAUGUGUGGGAAUUGUGGGAGCUACAAUUCAAGAUGAGAUUGGGUAGGCGGACACAGUCAAACCAUAUCAUUCUGCCCCUGGCCCCUCCCAAAUCUCAUGUCCUCACAUUUCAAAACUAAUCAUGCCUUCCCAACAGUCCCCCAAAGUUUUAACUCAUUUCAGCAUUAACUCAAAAGUCUACAGUCCAAAGUCUCAUCUGAGACAAGGCAAGUCCUUUCCACCUAUGACCUUGCAAAAUCAAAAGAAAUUGGUUACUUCCUAGAUACAAUGGGGGUACAGGCAUUGGAUAAAUACAUCCAUUCCAAAUGGGAGAAAUUGACCAAAACAAAAGGAUGAGGCUGUACCUAGAUAAAAGGCACUGACUACAUGGGAAUCGUCUUCCACCAUGAUUGUGAGGCCUCACCAGCCACAUGGAGCUGUGAGUCCAUUAAACCUUUUUUCUUUAUAAAUUAUCCAGUCUCAGGUAUGUCUUUAUCAGCAGCUUGAAAAUGGACUAAUACAAUGGUGCAGUGGAACUGUUGGGUCAAAUGUUAGCUUUACUUUUAAUUUUUUUGAGGAACCUCCAAACUGUUCUCCAUAGCAGUUUUACUAAAGGCCCCAUACAAUUCCAAAAUCCAGCAGGGAAGUCCAAUCUUAAAGCUCCAAAGUUAUCUCCUUUGACUGCAUGUCUCACAUUUGGGUCACAAUGAUGCAAAAGGUGGGUUUCCAUGCUCUUGGGCAGCUCUGCUUCUGUGGCUUUGCAGGGUACAGCCUCCCUCCUGGCUGCUUUUGUGACCUGGCAUUGAGUGUCUGCAGCUUUUCCAGGUGUGCAGUGCAAGCUGUCAAUGCCUUUACAAUUCUGGGGUCUGGAGGUCGAAGACCCUCUUCUCACAGCUCCACUAAGCAGUCUCCGAUGGAGACUCUGUGUAUGGACUUCAACCCCACAUCUUCCUUUCACACCGCCCAAGCAGAGGUUCUCCAUGAGGACCCCACCCCUGCAGCAAACUUCUACCUGGGCAUCCAGGCAUUUCCAUACAUCCUCUGAAAUCUAGGUGGAGGUUCCCAAACCUCAAUUCUUGACUUCUUUGCACCUGUAGGCUCAACACCACAUGGAAGCUGUCAAGGCUUGGGGCUUGCACCCUCUGAAGCCACAGCCUGAUCUGUACCUUGGCCCCUUUUAGCCAUGGCUAGAGUGGCUGAGACACAGGGCACCAAGUCACUAAGGCUGCACACAGCAGGGGCACCUGGACCUCCUAGGCCUCCAGGCCUGUGAUAGGAAGGGCUGUCACAAAGGUCUCUGACAUGCCCUGGAGACAUUUUCCCCAUUGUCUUAGGGAUUAACCUUUGGUUCCUCAUUACUUAUGCAAAUUUCUGCAGCAGGCUUGAAUUUCUCCUCAGAAAAUGGGUUUUUAUUUUCUAUCACAUCACCAGGCUGCAAAUUUUUCAAACUUUUUUGCUGAGUUUCCCUUUUAAAACUGACUGCUUUUAACAGCACCCGUCACAUCUUGAAUGCUUUGCUGCUUAAAAAUUUCUUCUGACAGAUACCCUAAAUCAUCUUACUCAAGUUCAAAGUUCCACAAAUCUCUAGGACAGGAGUAAACGCUGCCAGUCUCUUUACUAAAAUAUAGCAAGAGUCACCUUUACUCCAGUUACCAACAAGUUCUUCAUCUUCAUCUGAGACCACCUCAGCCUGGAUUUCAUUUUCCAUAUCAUUAUCAGCAUUUCAGUCAAAGCCAUUCAACAAGUCUCUAGGAAGUUCCAAACUUUCCAACAUUUUCCUGUCUUCUUCUGAGCCCUCCAAAUAUUGCCCCAGUUCCAAAGUUGCUUCCACAUUUGUGGGUAUCUUUACAGAAGCACUUCACUCUAUCAGUACCAAUUUACUAUAUUAGUCCAUUUCUCAUGCUGCUGAUAAAGACAUACCUGAGACUGGGUAAGUUAUAAAGAAAAGAGGUUUAAUGUACUCACAGUUCCACCUGGCUGGGGAAGCCUCACAAUCACGGCAGAAGGUGAAAGGCACAACUUACAUGGCAGCAGGGAAAAGAGAAUUUCUGCAGGGAAACUCCCCCUUAUAAAACCCUCAGAUCUCAUGAAACUUAUUCAGUAUCACAAGAAUAGCACGGGAAAGACCUGGCCCCAUGAUUCAAUUACCUCCCACAGGCUCCCUCCCAUGACAGGUGGGAACUAUGGGAGCUAUAAUUCAAGAUGAGAUUUGGGUGGGGGUGCAGCCAAAUCAUAUCAAAGGCAUAUACCCAAAAGAAAGGAAAUAAGUAUAUCAAAGACGUAUCUGCACUCCCACAUUUGUUGCAGAACUGUUCACAAUGGCCAAGGUUUGGAAGCAACCUAAGUGUCCAUCAGCAGAUGAAUUGAUAAAGAAAAUGUGGUACAUAUACACAAUGAAGUACUAUUCAGCCAUAAAAUAAAGAAUGAGAUCCUGUCAUUUGCAGCAACAUGGAUGGAACUGGAGAUCAUUAUGUUAAGUGAAAUAAGCCAGGCACAGAAAGACAAACAUCACAUGUUCUUGCUUAUUUGUGUGAGAUAAAAAUAAAAACAAUUGAACUCAUAGACAUAGAGAGAGAAGGAUGAUUACCAGAGGCUGAGAAGGGUAUUGGGUGCUUCAGGGGAAGUGGGAAUAGUUAAUGGGGGGAAAAAAGGAAGUUGGAAAGAAUGAAUAAGAUCUACUAUUUGAUAGCACAACAGGAUGACUAUAGUCAAUAAUAACUUAAUUCAUUUUUAAAUAACUAAAAAAGUAUAAUUGGAUUGUUUGUAAUCACAAAGAAUAAACGCUUGAGGGACAGAUACCCCAUGCUGCAUAAUGUGAUUAUUAAUAUCCAGUAUUUGAUAACACAACAGGGUGCUGUAGUCAAAAUAAUUUAAUUGUACAUUUUAAAAUAACUAAAGGAGUAUAACUGGAUUGUUUGUAACACAAAGGAUAAAUGACUGAGAAGAUGGAUACCCCAUUCUCCAUGACAAGAUAAUUACACAUUGCAUACCUAUAUCAGAACAUCUCAUACACCCCAUAAAUAUAUCCAUCUACUAUGUAGCCACAAAAAUUAAAAAUAAAACAUUUUAAAAUAUA